ACAUUGUAGCAAAAUGGCGACUGUCAUUCACAACCCCCUGAAAGCGCUCGGGGACCAGUUCUACAAGGAAGCCAUUGAGCACUGCCGGAGUUACAACUCACGGCUGUGUGCAGAGCGCAGCGUGCGUCUUCCCUUCCUGGACUCACAGACUGGGGUGGCCCAGAACAACUGCUACAUCUGGAUGGAGAAGAGGCACCGAGGCCCAGGCCUUGCCCCGGGCCAGCUGUAUACAUACCCUGCCCGCUGCUGGCGCAAGAAGAGACGAUUGCACCCACCUGAAGAUCCAAAACUGCGGCUGCUGGAGAUAAAACCUGAAGUGGAGCUUCCCCUGAAGAAGGAUGGGUUCACCUCAGAGAGCACCACGCUGGAAGCCUUGCUCCGUGGCGAGGGGGUUGAGAAGAAGGUGGAUGCCAGGGAGGAGGAAAGCAUCCAGGAAAUACAGAGGGUUUUGGAAAAUGAUGAAAAUGUAGAAGAAGGGAAUGAAGAAGAGGAUUUGGAAGAGGAUAUUCCCAAGCGAAAGAACAGGACUAGAGGACGGGCUCGCGGCUCUGCAGGGGGCAGGAGGAGGCACGACGCCGCCUCUCAGGAAGACCACGACAAACCUUACGUCUGUGACAUCUGUGGCAAGCGCUACAAGAACCGACCGGGGCUCAGCUACCACUAUGCUCACACUCACCUGGCCAGCGAGGAGGGGGAUGAAGCUCAAGACCAGGAGACUCGGUCCCCACCCAACCACAGAAAUGAGAACCACAGGCCCCAGAAAGGACCGGAUGGAACAGUCAUUCCCAAUAACUACUGUGACUUCUGCUUGGGGGGCUCCAACAUGAACAAGAAGAGUGGGCGGCCUGAAGAGCUGGUGUCCUGCGCAGACUGUGGACGCUCUGGUCACCCAACCUGCCUGCAGUUUACCCUGAACAUGACCGAGGCUGUCAAGACCUACAAGUGGCAGUGCAUAGAGUGCAAAUCCUGUAUCCUCUGUGGGACCUCAGAGAAUGAUGACCAGCUACUCUUCUGCGAUGACUGUGACCGAGGCUAUCACAUGUACUGUUUAAAUCCCCCGGUGGCUGAGCCCCCAGAAGGAAGCUGGAGCUGCCACUUAUGCUGGGAACUGCUCAAAGAGAAAGCCUCAGCCUUUGGCUGCCAGGCCUAGGGCCCCAGGUCACAGAAUGUGACUCGCUGCUGGAGAUCCUAAAGCAGAGCCCAGUUCAAACCAGAACGCGCCCUCCUCCCACAUAUCCAGCCAGACCAACUGCAAGGAAAAGAAAUAGUCCCAGAGGGGCAGGGACACAUGGAACGAAGAGGGUGAGGCAUCUCCUGACCUCCCCCGAUAUGUACGGAACUUCAGCCAGCACCUCCUUGUCUCUACCGGAAGGAAGUUGCACUUUGGGAGAACACCUCCGGCCCCAGCCCUGUGGAACCCCUCUCACUUUUACCCUAGCACCGAGGCCCUCUCAUUGGUUCCCAUUUUAAGGGAAGCCAUUUCCUGACCACUCAUCCAUUACUUGUGUGUAGUGUGGUGUUUUUUUAUCUAUUGUGUUCCAAGAAAUCUUGGCACAGCCCCCGUGCCCCCAGCUUAGGGUCUGCAUCCUGAAAUUCUCACCUGAGGAACAAAGGGCUGUGGAGAAGUUGUCGUUUAUGGCAAGCCUCACUGGAAACUUCUAGACUUGGGGUCUUGAAACCCUUUCUUGUUCCUUGGUGUCUGUGGAGACAAAGAGUUGCCUUCUAGAACCCCAGCAGUGGCAUCCACAGCCAGCCUGGUCUUGAGCCACUGCUUAAAGUUACUAGAUGGGGGCGGGGAGGGAGGGAGACGCGCAGAGACAUGGGAGGAAACAUUGUGGAAAUGGUGCCAAGGCCCCGCCAUAGCCAGUCAGUACUUGUUAUCCAUCGGGAGAGACUUUGCAAGAGGCCAGGCUGGUUCCUUGACCUUCAGAGCUGGGGCAUCCUUUAGGUGAGACCAGUCAUGGCCUAUGGACAGAGGAAGACGGUCAAGCCUCUGCCUCUCAGCCCACCUGGUUCUGGAGACCUGGUUCAGCUUCUCCUGGUGGGACUGAAGAACCAGGAAGGGGAGCGAAGGCUGCCCAAUCAUGUGUCCGAAUGCUGGAUACAGGGGGCUGCAGCUUUGAGAAACCUUCAGUAUUGAUGCGACGCUCUGAAUUCCUUUUUCCAAGUAAUUUCUUCCUUCCACGUAGUGUUUGUUCGCUAUUGUCUACUGAGACCUGACUGGGAAUUUUAGGAUGGGGGAGAGAAGAUUGUUAUCUAAACAAAUAAUUAGGGUGACAUGGUCAUUAUUCACGACCAGGGUGGCCACAUUUUAGAACUCUCAGUGCGGGGGCUGCUCUUGUCUCCUAAGCUCCCCAAACAUGCAGGACUCUUGUUUUCAAAAAAAAAUGUGUCUAGAAGAAAGAGGUGGGGAGGCUGAGCUUCCGAGAACUCUGUGUGUUGGAAGAUAGCCCCGAGGGCUGGAGCGGAUUGGGCUGACUUUGAAUCGCAGCAGCAGCACAAUAACUGACAUAUUUCUGGAAAAAUCAUUUGCCCAAAGGGCAGGUCUCGGUGAGCGGAACCCUCGCGCAUGCUUGGCUUCUCUGAAAUCAGCUCCAUCUCUGUGGUCUGGCUGCUCACAACAAAGGCCCAGGUUAUUUUUAGUUCUUCAGCUCCUGAGGACGCUCCCGGAGACUCGGGCUAGUUGGGCCACCUCUGCCCGGCCGCAGUAUUUGUGCUGUCCCUCGGCAGGAGUGCUCCUCUCUAGGCUAAUUGCUCUUGGCCAGUGGACCCAGGGCAGCCUGGCAUGAAACCAAGCAGUGUGGGUCUCCCCCACGCUUCAGCAGAGUGACCUGUGGCAAGCGAUGGGGGUCACUCUCCUGCAGGGGCCUGUGGCCUCAGAGGGAAUCACACACAUACAUAAUGGUCUCAUUUAAAGGGCCCCCGACCGGAUGGAAUUUUCAUCUUCCUCAUAAGUAAUUUCCUUCCGCCUGCUGGUCGGUGAGCUUGUCUGAAUCCUGAAGGCCCAGGGAGGGAUAGGGAGGGUGACAUUCCAUCAGAGGGGCACAUUUUUUCUCCUGACUACUCCAGCUCUCUCUCUUCCCACAAAACCCAAAGCAGGCUGUCUCCAAAGGCUAAUAAUUGGUUUUGAGCGUCAUUUUAAUUUAAAUUUAGAAAAAAAAGUUCCCCAAAUGUUCCCAAGUGCCACAAUAGCUUAAAAGUUUAAAAAGCAAGUCCGAAACCCCAAACUGUGGCUCUACAACUUCACACGUCCUCUUCAGAGUAUGUGCAAAUUUGUUUUCCACAGAAGUGCAGGUGAUAGGGCAGCCCUGUUCGAUCUCAGCCCCAUGUCUGCUCUGCCUACACAAGCUGAGCCUCAGCUGGGUCUCCCAGGCCAAGGCAGGGCACUGGAACUUGCCUGCACUGGUGAGGGUCAGGGCUCUGGAGUGACGUUAGGAUGGCCCCGGAGUUCCCCUCUCAGCUUCAUUACUCCCUGAAGAAUGGGCCCAACCCAUUCUUCAUCUUUGGAGGCCUCAGUUUCCCCAUCUGGAAAGCGGGGAUAGCAAGCCAGCUUGUGGGCUGGCACUGUCAGGGUACUACAAGCAGACAAAAGUCUCCGUGGUCACAUUUAUCACCUCUGUGUUCAAAAGAGGACGGGGUUGGUAAACUUUAAAUUGGUCUCUUUUUUUUGAACCCCAGAGAAUGAGAUAGAAUCAUAGGAUGCAUGUGAAGGAUCAGAGUUUUUGUGUUGCCUCUGCCAUGGAGUAGCUGUGUGACACUGGGCAAGUCACCUAACCUCCCUGAACCUCAAUUGCCCACCUGGAAAGUGGAGAUAGUAACACUUGCCCUGCCUAUUCCAGAGUGACACUGGGACUCUUAAGCAUCAUGUUACAUAAACAAGCACUGCAGAGCCAUGCUUGUCUGGGAAGAACUCCGGAUGUUUUCCAUGUCCGCCUUCUUGUGUGCAUUAGCCAAUGUUAGACGUCUUCUUCAAAUCUCCCUUGUGACCAAAGGGAGUUUAUAUUGCCAGGGCUGGGCUGCGACCAAGGAAAUCAUGACUUGCAUGGGCUGUGGGGUGGAGGUGAGGGAUGUACAUGGGGUUGGGGACUUUAAAAUGAAGGUACUCAGGAUACUCCUUCUAUAAGAUUAAUGCAGUUGAGAAUGGAAAGGUGACUUUUAGAGAGGGCUAUGAUUUGUUUCAGUUCAUGGGUAACGCUCACUUUCCGACCAACACUGCCACUUUCUAGCUGACUGACCUUGGGCCAAUGACUUCAACUCUCUGAGCCUCAUUUCACAUGUCUGUAAGGUGGGGAAACAUGGCCUAUCCAGCAUGGUCUUUGCAGGUAUUCAAGGUGACAUUGGUAAAGAUCCUGGCCCGGGUCUGGCAUGAUGAUGGUCCCCACUCCAUGGUAGCUAUUGUCAUUUUCUGCAGAGGCCACCAAAUGGAGAUAAUGAUGUGGUUGUCUUCCGGCUCAAAUGCUGGGAACAGCCAGGAGAACUUUGCUGGGCUUCACCCCUCUGUACUGUGGCUCCAGCAAACCAGAGAGGUGAGGCUGCCAGACCCAACCGGAAGUGGAAAUCCUGUUUCCUGUAGGCAUUUUUGAAACCCUGCUUUUUGGAUCUGUAGCAAAUCCAGUGCAGGCAACAUUAUGUGGAAAUAGAAACAGGGCUCCUGCUAGGAGAUUGACAUUCUGGCUUUCCUUUGGAACCCCUCACUGACUCAUCGCCCCUGAAGCAGGAGCCAGCAGGUCCCAAGGCUCCCCUGCUCCUGUCCCUGCCCCAGGGCGAGGUAGGAAGCCGGAAGCCUGGGCAGGCUGAGCCCAGCCGACUGGAACCAGGGAAGAGCCUGUGGGUGGGUGGAAGGGAGGGAAGGAGGCCAGAUUCCUCCAGAACUGGGGAAGAGAACAGGUUUUGAAGUUGGGGGAGGGUUUGGGUUUCACAGUGAUGGUUUCAUGAUACCCUGGAGGGUUGCACACUCCUGGUGCAUUUUUGUAUUCGUGCUUUGAAUACAGCCCGCUUCCUUUCAACCCUCCGCUUAAAAAGUUUUGAUGUUUUAAGGAAGAAAAAUGAGAUGAUUGUUAUUACUUUUCCUUUCGGGGCAAGUGGAGGAGACCUGUGCUCUUUUAUGCCGCUGAAGAAAGGUUGCUGGCAACCUCAGGCCUCAGGACUCAAAGAAGAGGGGCUUAUAGUCUCCUCUUUGGGUCUGUGUGUGAGGAGGUAGGGGGUGUUGCGCCGCCCGUGGCCCAGGGCGGGCCCUGAGGACCACAUCCCUGCCCCCCAGGCUGGUUUUUAGCCUGUCGUGGAAGUGCUGGGACAGAAGCAGCCCCUUCUUCUCUCACUCCCCGGCUGCCCCUCCUAGCCCCUCUUCAGGGGGUCCCCAUGUCUCAGCCCGAGGGAGAAGUUGGCUCUGGCCAGAGCCACGCUCACACUCCCACAGGAUGCCGCAAGUCCCAGGCCUGGCUCCUGGUAGCAGUGGUGACUUGGUGUCCCUUUUAGCAGGCUUCCAUUCCUGGGGAGGGAGAAAGACAGGGGUGCCUGGGGAAGGGAGGGUGGGAGGGCAUUUGGGAGGGGUGAGGAUCUCUGGUGGAAAAAGGCAGAGAGCUGGAUGUCCUCAGGGAGAAAUCCUCGAGCUAAGGAGCUGGAGGGCAGCAGGUGGGAGUGAACAGUGAUUGUAACUCUUUUUUUUUUUUCUGAGGCUUGUGAUCCUGGGCAACAGAUUAUUAUUAUUAUUAUUUUGUAAAAAGGCCAAACCUCUGCCCAGUUCUGAACACUGAUUCAGCUCCCUCUUUCUUGAGGCCGCCCGUUGGUUGUGUGGGGUUUCAGGGAUGCUUCUGAGGGCAAAGUAAGCCCCUCACCCAGCUGGGGAGAGAAGGCAGUGAGGGAGGGCUGGAUCAUGCCUGCAGCCUUGGGGAGUGAAGCAUUUCCAGGCACUGCUACCAGAGGGGUCAGGCCCCCAGGCCCCUGUCCCCCAAGCCCAGGACACCAGUAGCUGGGAAGGGAAGAGGGGGACUGGCCAUCCUGCUCCUCUCCCCUCUGCAAAGUGGACAGAGCUCCUCCUCUUCCUGCUGUGUGUUGCCCGUUUUGAAAUCUUACUCCCAUCCCCAAAGUAUGCUUUUGGAUACCAGGUGAAGGGGAAGGAUGGUGAUGGUGGGGAACAGCUGUUUUAAUUUGCCUCAGGCCUAUGAAUCUCCCUACCUGAACCCCAGCUUGCCAUAGAGUCUAACUGGUCCGUGGUCAGAAGGUGGGCUCCAUAGCUGUCUGGGGGUUGGGGCUCCCUCCCCCAUUUCUGAGCAUUCCCAGGGUUUGGGAGUCUGCUUAUGAUUCUCUGCCAGAGGCCACGGCCACCAGCCCUGAGUGUGGAAACAAUGGGACAGAUGGGUUGGUUCAAGGCCUUUGGGCAGCUGGUGGUGGGUCUUGGAGAGCUGGGAACCCCUUCCUAGGGAGGCUGGAGACCCUCUGGUCUGUGAGUGGACAGCUGAGAGUGGGGCAGGGGGAAGGAGGGGAGAGGAAGAUGGGGGUGCUUCCUGCUGGGCACCCGGGAUGUGGGAGGAUAGACAACCUCCCAGGCAGAGCGAGUGGGAACUGCCUUAGAGCCUCUCAGCAGCUGUCCCCGGGGAGGCCUGGCUGUGCGGCGGGCGCCCCCUCCAUGUGCGCAGCCCAGGCAGCUAGAAGAGAGGCCCAAAGGAAGAGCUGUCAGGAAACUCUGAGGAGGAGGGGUCCGGGCUUGCCAGUUCCGUACCAUGGGUUUUCUAGAAGGAACAGGGAACUCCCUGCAUGAGGGGAAAGAUUUGGAAGUGAGUGGGUUCCUGGGAACAGGCUCUCUCUGGGUUCUGAGUGAGCCCUGGCUGUGAGGGGGUCCUGAGGUGACUCCCCAGGGCCCUUUGUUCCAGCUUCUGUCCCCACUCCUUCCCUUUCUCUGCUCCAGUGCCAACCUCAGGUCAUAGGGCAGGUGGCCUUGAGAGAGGGACCUUCCACAGUUCCCCUUCUUUGGCUCCACCAGGAGAAGGGAGUAUUUUGCUGAUGGCGACAUUUCCCAGGGCAGGCCAGAGGAAGGCAGGAACCAGGACUGGCAGGCAGCCAGAACCCUCUUGGACAGAGAUAUAAUUACUUAUCAUGACCUCUAGCCCAGGCAUUGAGCAAAAUGGCCCUGUAGGCUGGCACCAACCCUGUCUAGCAAAUAAACGCGGCCAUGGUGGGGACGGGAGGGCAGGUAAGUGGGCCUUGUAGGAAAUGGCAGAGGCCUGUGAGCCCCUGGGGCCUAUAUAUUCCCUCAGCAACACAACCCUACAGACUCCCAGGUUAUAUUUUCACUCACUGCAUCCCAUUUGCUCAUUUGCUCGCCUCUCUGCAUCUCUGUUCUUCAUUUCAAUGUUAUGAAUAUUGAUGAUGAGAACAGGAAUGCCCAUGUGCAUGCGCGUGCGUGCACGCACGCACAUACACACACACACACACACACACACACACACACACACACGCCCUACUUAAUGAACCAAAGGGAAACUUUGAUGUUGCUCCAGGACAAGAGGGAGAGCCAGGGGCUGCCAGGCAAGGUGCAUCUUUCCUGAAGUCUUCUCCAGUCCUGCUCCUCCAGCUCUCAGCCUCUGCACAGCCACCAGGGUUGCAAAGGGAGCCUUGUGCUUGGAAAGCUACUGGCUCCGCGACCUCUCUCCUUCUCUUCCCUUCGUUCACCUAUGCUUCUUUUCAUGAAAGAUAUUUGGCAAUAGUUGGGUACUUCAAAAGUCUCAAUUCUGCUAUCAAAGGGAUGCAAAGCUUUUAUGGCUAGAAUGGGGUUUGUGGUUUAUACGGACUUGGUUUGCCCUUCCAUGUCUACUCCCCACUGAGACCCUGAUUCUCCUCCUGCCCUCUCCCUUCCCUGCACUGUUUCCUCCCUUCCCUCUGCCGUGAUAGAUGCUAAGGAGUGGGGUGGAGGUGGGAAGUGGGAAGCAACAGUGGCGUAUAGGAAAAAGAAAAUAUACCCCGUGCACAUUUUCAACAUGUAGUUGAAGAAGCCUAAAUUAGGUACUAGAAAAAAAAAAAGGACAGAAACACUGCCUGAUAUGUGAGCAAGAGCAUGAAAAUAUAGAAUGAUUAUCUCAGAGCAGAGGAGGUGGGGAGCAGGUGGCUGGAGAGAGGCGGGGUAGGUAGGCAGGGCGUCCCUGGCUCACCAAUGCGUCUGGUCCACAUGGCAUUUGGGAAAGCAGAUGGGUCAUGCUUUUGCAAUGAAUGGUCAGAUGCUUAGGGGGCAUUUGUGCUCCUCUGGCCAGGAAAGGGAACAGAGUCCAUCCAAGCUGCCCCCCACUCAUCUGCCAUGGUUGUCCACCCUGGGGGUUUUUCCUCUGAAGGAAAAUGAACCCAUCUUUUGCCUGCCAUGAAUCAUUGCAGGGCAGGCUGUUACUGGCUAAAUUAAAACCCUUGGCAGGGCAUCGACUGUGUGCGAGGCAAUGCUCUAGGUCCUGUAGGGGCUGGAAAAUAAACCGCAUGCUGGCCUAGCCUUCAAGUUGCUUUUCAGCCAUGAAAUUAAGCUCUGCCAAGCAAUCGUGAUUGUAGGUCAAGUAUCGCGCCAUCACGGAAGGUGUAAGUAUAUGUAGGUUUCUCUGUUGAGGAUGCGUGUUCCUCAGUAGAAGACAAGCAGGUGGAGGCAUCCAGUGAUUUCUACCCUGUGGAGGCUGAGGGGUCGGGGGAAGAAAACAGAUGACCUCAGCCUAGUUGCUUUAAUCUGCUUUUCCAAGCACUGGAUGCCCUUGGAUGACAGCAUCCUCAGCAUUAAAACUGGUGAACUGAUGAAGUCACCUGGCCUGGAGUGUGUUGGGCAGCCAGUGUCCCCAGAGCUGCUUGUGGGUUUCUGGGGUGGAAGGCAGGGAGGUGCAACUGGCAGGGCCUGAUCAGAGGCAGAAAAUGACCCCCACAGUGGUCUUUUCCCUGCUAGAGAAAGCAGAGAGCGGGACUGGGGGGGUGGGGGCUUCAAGUACAGAUUGGGCACACUCCACCAGACCCCAGCAAGGUCAGCUGCCCCACGCCUGUAUCUGGCACUGCUGGUGUGUGCAGGGAUGAAACCCAGCAUCAGAGAGGUUUUCAGCAAACCUUCCAUGCUCACCUUUGGCCAGGUGCUUGUCAGAUCCUAGCUUCGUGCUGGCUUAGACUCUCAGUUGUUUGUGUUGACAGCAUUAGGAAUAAACCGUUUGUUUCAUCUUUCCUUUUCUCCACACGUGUCACAGCCAGAUUUCAGCUUUGAGUUAUUCCCUGAAGAAGCCACACCAACCUUGCUUUCAAGCAAAAUGCCUGGGCUUGGGGGAAGGUGUGUAUCUGUCCAUGUGUGGAUGUUGGCUCAGAGCUAUAGCUUCUCUGUGGGGGGUGGCCCAAGGGAAGGCUCCUCUGGGGCCCUGGAUGGCACAUGACUCCCAGUGAGGAGAAUUCUGGUGAUCUCUGUGGAGGUAGUCAGGGACACAAGGCUUGGCUGUGAGUCUGGUUUUAAAGUGCGUGACAGCCUGAAAAGCAUGCAGGGGUUUGGUCCACUCACCUACUUGAAAGCCUGUGGGCAACGUUCUUUUGAGCCAAGACUUCUCUGAAUGGCCCUGCUGGUGGAAGGGGUGAGGCAAAGGCCUCUGACUUGGACCCUUUCCACACCAGACUGGCAGCACUUCCCCCAGGCAGCCAGUGGUGGGCCCUGAGCCCUCAGGUCCCCAGCUCCUUGAGGGAUGAACCUGGGAGCCCAAGAGCCAGUGGCUGAGCUCUGAGAAGGCUCCAUCUCCCACCUGCCCUUGAGCGCGCUCUCAGGCUGAGAACACGGUCUCAUCAGGCGCCUUCCUGGCCUGAUGCUGUGCUGUCUACGUCACACGGUCGAUUCACAAAAGCCAGAACUAGACCUCAACCAGGUCAUCUCCCCGUUGCCAAGUGGGUUCAGGGUGAGGGCAAUUUGUAAGCUCAAUUUCUCUGACAGCCAAGACAUGGAGCAUCUCUGCUAAGAAGCCAAAAGAAAUUGGUUUUCUUCUUCUCAUUGCUGAAGCCCCUCUGUGUCUCUUCUCAGGGACAGGCUGGUCCAGUGGCUUUGGUGAGGGCGCCUCCAUUUGUGAACGCUGGGAUUCCUCUGGGUGGGCUUUGGCAGGUGGCUCCUAUGGUAGGAAGGAUGACCAGGUCCCUGGGAAUGAGCUGCCUACCUGCUGCUCCACGAGGAAGCUCAGGCCUGCACAGGCUCCACCAGGCCUUGGAUGCCCUCUAGUUGAGUCAGAGACCCUGGAAACACACUGAGAUCUCCAAUUGCUGCCUCCAUUGAUGUCUCUAGACCUGCAGAUACGAAGCAAACCUGGGAUUGCUUCUUCCAGGUAUGGGCACCAGAGAGGGAAGCCACUGCAACAUUUUAUCCCCAUCAUUCCAAAAUGCUUGCUUGUCUCUUUUACCUCACACUCACAACUCCUUCUGAGACUCUCAGUCAUAAAGGAAUGACCAAGAGAGUGGGUCUCCAGUGAGAGAAAUGCCUAUGAAAGAGGGUUUCCCUUUUUGCUCUUUUGAACACCCUCCCCACUGAUCCUUGGGACCCAACGCCGCAUUGCCUCUUGCAGAUGAGGUUUUGCCUUGGGCUGCUUUGGUACUUCAGACCAGGACUGAGUCUGACACAGCUUUCAUGAGGUUACAGAAAAGGGCUACAGAUUUGGGAAGCUGUGUGUAAUGGUCUUGAGACAAUAUCUCCAUUUGGCCCACCCUGGCUUCUCUAAAAAGCAACGACAGCAACAGACAAACAAAAAGCUCCCACCUCCCACCCCGUUAGCUGUCCUCCUCCUUCACUGUGAUGUGGUUGCGGUCUCUGUAGGUGUGUGUGCCACCCUUGUCCUCUGUCCUCUGGGGAUGUGCCCUUCCCACGUGUGUCAGGUUCCCACUCUUUCGUGGUUCCUAACGUGAAGUGCUGUGAUGUUUCUGCCCUGCCUAAGGAACGUAUCAAGCUCUCUCAGUGUUUCAGUGUUGGAGAUUGAGGCUGUGCCACAUCUUCUGCCAUCCUAAGGGGACAUGAUGGUUCUGUGAUUCCCAGAGAGCUGGCAGAUUGUGACAAUCUCCAGGAGAACCUACAGAUUGGAAGCAGCCCACACCUGAUGUGGACUCCUGACCCGGGACUCACUCUUCAUUCAGAAGACUGGUGGCCCACGUGCCAGGACCACCCCACCUCUCUUGCUGCCUUUUCUCCUGUCCUGAUGGGGUUCUGGGAGGGAGACCUGUCGCUGAUGAGAUGAAGAAUGUGGGGAUCGAGCAGCCUUCUUCUUUGGGACCCCUCGAUAUCCCAUGGAAUGCUCGCACGUUCUCAAAGACUGAGUCACAAGCCCCUACCCCUUCCUUGCUGUGGUUAGUAUCUUGUUCUGUGAUUGGUUAGCAAUGUUGACUACCCACGUAGUGAAUCUUUUGUCUGCAAUUUAGAGAAUGUGUAAACAAAUAAAAGGCUUUAAAACUC